AUAGUUCCCUGCGGCCUCUGCCUUGGGGAGUUAUGUUUUGUUACCGAGAUCCGCGCUACCAGAUUGCACCGGGGCUGAUUUGGGGGCUGGGAAUUUGCCAUUCUGCUGUACAGACACUGAUUUUUUUUUCUUCUUUUUAAAAAGCAAGGUUUGUUUUCAUUUUGGUUUCUGUCGGAUUUUCUCAUUUGUAACUCACUUUUCUAUUUUUACUUUUCUUAACCGGAAGAUCUUUUCAUUAUCCCACCUCUUCAUCUUGCUUUUAACCUGAUUUCCUAUUAUAUAAUUAAUGCUUAAAUCUCACAAGGGUUGGUCGGUGCGGGGCUGGUGUGUCCUUUUGUAGAUGAAAGUUUAAGACCUCUUAACUGGUUUCAGUCUAUUUGUCUGGUUUCAAAAUAAGGGUAAUUGCAACCAAAUAUCCCUCUUUAGCUUCUCGAUCAAGUCGAUUCCUCCCCCAUAUAUGAUUCAAAUGGCAAUUUUAUUAAACUGAAAACUAGUACCUGACUUGCAGCGUCAGCAUUUGGAAAGUGCUUGUCGGCAAAUCGACUGUAUGAAGGCGUGUAGCUUCAUCCCCUGCCAUUUUUGUGGGUUCUAGCACUUUAAAAAAUUGUCUGGUAAUUUCUUGGACUUAACCCUGUGUCUUUGGUUGUAGAGCAGCACUAACCAGGGGAGUAAUAUGGUUGGCACUUCGUGUCCAGAACUCCGUAUUUCAGGCUGGGAAACACCUAAUUAAUGUCUGGGAAACAAGAAGAUGAUUUAUCCUGAGUACCUCUGUCCUCAGCUUCUGCAGACACAGUUUAAAUAUGGAAACUGUUUCUCCUUCUUCCUGUGCCUCAGUUUCCAUAGAACAAACUGUAAUUGCAUAGCACAGCUUCAGGAACCUGCAGAUAUAAGUUAAUGUUAUAAUGUGCAGUGAAGAUGAAAACUGCUUAGCUAAGUCUAAGUCUGUAAGUCAAUGAGAUUUCCUUUUUAACAAAUCAGUUAUCCAGGUUUCCUGCUUUGACUGUCUGAUAUAGUAAUGCUUAUGCUCAACUGGUAUAAGAAUUGCUGCUUUACAUUGCUUUGAAAUUAAGCUUACACUUAAAAUAGUAAUUUAUUCUGUUGGUAAUAUUGUCGAGCUGAAGUUUGCAGGUUCUUGUUAUCUUAGACCUCCUAAUUCUCUAUUCUCGUCUGUGGCAGUGUCCACUUUUCCGUUUAAACUUUUUAUUUAACACAUCUUCAGUUGAAGUGAAAUAUUUUAAGAAUACAGGUAUGUUUUUGCGUACCCUGCUUUAUAUGGGACUAUAAGCCUCAACUUGGUAUUUUUUUUUUUUUUGUAUUCUUUUGUUUACUUGUCCCCCUUACUCUUCUCUAUGGGAUUGGGUGUGGUUAAGUUGGAUAUUCAGGUAUUUGGGGUUUAGUCAUAUGUUCCACAGUGAGAUUCCAGAUACUGUCCCCUGAUGUCUUAAAGAAAAAUUGUGAACCUUCCAGAAUUAACUGGAAAUGAACGACAAAGUUAAUUAGGAGAUUAAACUUGCAUCAUUUCUGCUUUUGCUCAAUGCUUUUGAAAAAAGGCUACUAAGAGCAAAAGACUUCCUUUAAGAAUUUACAGGGCAUUUACAAGAGGGGGAGAUGGAGGAAGACUUUGCAGGUGAUUCAAAGAUUAUAUUGUUUUGAUGCAGCUUCUGUCACUGUCUUCAUUUCUCUGUAACUGUUUCUGCAAACUUGGGUGCUGACCCAUUAAGAGCCCAGCUGCUUCAGUACCCAGUCUCAAGGGUAAGGAGGAGAAGCCAAGGGAAAGUAACUUACAGGGAGAAAGAAAUGCUUAUCCACUAGCUUUACUACACCACAAGGCAUGGAGUUUCCACAGAGCACCUGUAAUUUAACCCUGAGGCUGCCCUGGUUCACCCCUUCGCUUUACUUUACAGGGACACUGACUGUCAUUUCUAAGGAAGAACUAAGAAAAAAAAAAGUCCUUUUAUACCAGUAAAACAUUUCUCUACAUUGUCUUCUGACAUAUGCGGGGGGAACAAUAUUCAGGAAAGGGAAAUACUUUAGCAAAUGUGCUUAACAUUCAGGUGUUCUUUAGGACAGUCAUGAAACAUGGGGAGACUGGGAGAAUUAUUAUUGUUUACCUCUCUGUAAAGUGUCCAGAGUAUUAUUAAAUUUGUUCCCCUCUUUCCUUUGCCCAACCAAUACACUAUUAAAAUAGGACUACAAUCAAUGCAAUUCCAUAUCAUAACCCCAGGGGUGGUGAGACUAAGCCAGCAUGCCUUACAUAACCAUUAAGUAAGACAUUUUAACAUUCAGGUACAUUACAUUCCACUUUUAUUUAGCAGACACGGUUUUCAUUGUGUAAUAAAAUAUUUUUAUUUGAUAGUCUGUCCUUGCUUAUAGCCUCAUGUAAUCAAGGGGACAGCAUGUUUAAGACUUUGUAUCCAGAACUUUAAGGUCUAGCUGUGGUUCGCUUAUUAAUAAUUCACUGGGAAGGUUAAUUUCUAGUUUUCUGCUGGGUCUCCCAGACCAUACUUCAAAUGUAGAAUAUGUUUCUUCUUUCUCCUAUGCCUCAGUUUCCACAAAACACACCCUUAGAGAAUUGUGUGUGUUCAACAAAGAUCUUUAACUAUAAGAGCAUUUCUGAGCCGCCACUUCAUCCUGGGACCAAAUUCUAAGAGCAAUUUGUAUUGAGCUAUAAACAGCUAAUCUGCUAGUUUAAGAUGUUCUUUUAUACAGUCAUGCAGAAAAAUGGAAAUUGUGUGUUCUAAUCCUUGGAGACUGGCUGAUAAAGUGUCACUAGGCCCCUGAUGAAAUUUAAUAUUUAGGCUUAUAUCCCCUUAAUUUUCCCCCUAAAUUUCUACAGUACGCUUUUACUGCAUGAUGAUACAGCUUUAUUUUGAACAGUGACCAAAUGUGUUCUUUACAAAGAAUAUUGACGAGUUGUGUAGUCUUGAACACGUUGCCUGACUUCUCUGUGCCCCAGUUUCCUAAUUCUUUAUUCUAUUCUGUGGCAGUGUCCACUUUUUGGUUUAAAGUUUUUAACACAUCUCCAGUUGAGGUGAAAGAUUUUAGGAAUACAGGUAUGUUUUUGCAUACCCUGCUUUAUACAGGACUACAAGUAUCAACUUGGUAACUUUUUGUACUAUUUUGUUUACUUAUCCCCCUUACUCCCCUCUUAAAUGGGAUUGGGCGUGGUUAGGUUGGAUAUUCAGGUAUCUUUUGGUACAGUGAGUGACCAUUUUCAGAAUGUUGUCUAACCAGUUAAUAGAUACUGGUAUCAGUAGUAGUAGUAAUUUUGAACUGUAAAAAUAAAGGUUGUUUUUAUGACUAAAAUAAACUACUUCAUGUGUUCAUUCGUUUUGCUGUUUAUCUAUAUUAAUAUUUCAAAUUAUUGCUUAGUCAAAACCUCAAGGUAUUAGUCACUGGUUUUUGAGCUUAUAAAGGAAGCCACUGGAGCAAGAUAUAAAAUUAACCAUUGAUGUUAGUCCAGAGUUCAAAAGGAUUUUAGGUGAUGGGCAAGUCAGAAAGUCAGAUGGAUAUAACUGAUAUCAACACUCCAAAGCCAAAGAAGAAACAGCGAUGGACUCCACUGGAGAUCAGCCUCUCGGUCCUUGUCCUGCUCCUCACCAUCAUAGCUGUGACAAUGAUCGCACUCUAUGCAACCUACGAUGAUGGUAUUUGCAAGUCAUCAGACUGCAUAAAAUCAGCUGCUCGACUGAUCCAAAACAUGGAUGCCACCACUGAGCCUUGUACAGACUUUUUCAAAUAUGCUUGCGGAGGCUGGUUGAAACGUAAUGUCAUUCCCGAGACCAGCUCCCGUUACGGCAACUUUGACAUUUUAAGAGAUGAACUAGAAGUCGUUUUGAAAGAUGUCCUUCAAGAACCCAAAACUGAAGAUAUAGUAGCAGUGCAGAAAGCAAAAGCAUUGUACAGGUCUUGUAUAAAUGAAUCUGCUAUUGAUAGCAGAGGUGGAGAACCUCUACUCAAACUGUUACCAGACAUAUAUGGGUGGCCAGUAGCAACAGAAAACUGGGAGCAAAAAUAUGGUGCUUCUUGGACAGCUGAAAAAGCUAUUGCACAACUGAAUUCUAAAUAUGGGAAAAAAGUCCUUAUUAAUUUGUUUGUUGGCACUGAUGAUAAGAAUUCUGUGAAUCAUGUAAUUCAUAUUGACCAACCUCGACUUGGCCUCCCUUCUAGAGAUUACUAUGAAUGCACUGGAAUCUAUAAAGAGGCUUGUACAGCAUAUGUGGAUUUUAUGAUUUCUGUGGCCAGAUUGAUUCGUCAGGAAGAAAGAUUGCCCAUCGAUGAAAACCAGCUUGCUUUGGAAAUGAAUAAAGUUAUGGAAUUGGAAAAAGAAAUUGCCAAUGCUACGGCUAAACCUGAAGAUCGAAAUGAUCCAAUGCUUCUGUAUAACAAGAUGACAUUGGCCCAGAUCCAAAAUAACUUUUCACUAGAGAUCAAUGGGAAGCCAUUCAGCUGGUUGAAUUUCACAAAUGAAAUCAUGUCAACUGUGAAUAUUAGUAUUACAAAUGAGGAAGAUGUGGUUGUUUAUGCUCCAGAAUAUUUAACCAAACUUAAGCCCAUUCUUACCAAAUAUUCUGCCAGAGAUCUUCAAAAUUUAAUGUCCUGGAGAUUCAUAAUGGAUCUUGUAAGCAGCCUCAGCCGAACCUACAAGGAGUCCAGAAAUGCUUUCCGCAAGGCCCUUUAUGGUACAACCUCAGAAACAGCAACUUGGAGACGUUGUGCAAACUAUGUCAAUGGGAAUAUGGAAAAUGCUGUGGGGAGGCUUUAUGUGGAAGCAGCAUUUGCUGGAGAGAGUAAACAUGUGGUCGAGGAUUUGAUUGCACAGAUCCGAGAAGUUUUUAUUCAGACUUUAGAUGACCUCACUUGGAUGGAUGCCGAGACAAAAAAGAGAGCUGAAGAAAAGGCCUUAGCAAUUAAAGAAAGGAUCGGCUAUCCUGAUGACAUUGUUUCAAAUGAUAACAAACUGAAUAAUGAGUACCUCGAGUUGAACUACAAAGAAGAUGAAUACUUCGAGAACAUAAUUCAAAAUUUGAAAUUCAGCCAAAGUAAACAACUGAAGAAGCUCCGAGAAAAGGUGGACAAAGAUGAGUGGAUAAGUGGAGCAGCUGUAGUCAAUGCAUUUUACUCUUCAGGAAGAAAUCAGAUAGUCUUCCCAGCCGGCAUUCUGCAGCCCCCCUUCUUUAGUGCCCAGCAGUCCAACUCAUUGAACUAUGGGGGCAUCGGCAUGGUCAUAGGACACGAAAUCACCCAUGGCUUCGAUGACAAUGGCAGAAACUUUAACAAAGAUGGAGACCUCGUUGACUGGUGGACUCAACAGUCUGCAAGUAACUUUAAGGAGCAAUCCCAGUGCAUGGUGUAUCAGUAUGGAAACUUUUCCUGGGACCUGGCAGGUGGACAGCACCUUAAUGGAAUUAAUACACUGGGAGAAAACAUUGCUGAUAAUGGAGGUCUUGGUCAAGCAUACAGAGCCUAUCAGAAUUAUAUUAAAAAGAAUGGCGAAGAAAAAUUACUUCCUGGACUUGACCUAAAUCACAAACAACUAUUUUUCUUGAACUUUGCACAGGUGUGGUGUGGAACCUAUAGGCCAGAGUAUGCGGUUAACUCCAUUAAAACAGAUGUGCACAGUCCAGGCAAUUUCAGGAUUAUUGGGACUUUGCAGAACUCUGCAGAGUUUUCAGAAGCCUUUCACUGCCGCAAGAAUUCAUACAUGAAUCCAGAAAAGAAGUGCCGGGUUUGGUGAUCUUCAAAAGAAGCAUUGCAGCCCUUGGCUAGACUUGCCAACACCACAGAAAUGGGGAAUUCUCUAAUCGAAAGAAAAUGGGCCCUAGGGGUCACUGUACUGACUUGAGGGUGAUUAACAGAGAGGGCACCAUCACAAUACAGAUAACAUUAGGUUGUCCUAGAAAGGGUGUGGAGGGAGGAAGGGGGUCUAAGGUCUAUCAAGUCAAUCAUUUCUCACUGUGUACAUAAUGCUUAAUUUCUAAAGAUAAUAUUACUGUUUAUUUCUGUUUCUCAUAUGGUCUACCAGUUUGCUGAUGUCCCUAGAAAACAAUGCAAAACCUUUGAGGUAGACCAGGAUUUCUAAUCAAAAGGGAAAAGAAGAUGUUGAAGAAUACAGUUAGGCACCAGAAGAACAGUAGGUGACACUAUAGUUUAAAACACAUUGCCUAACUACUAGUUUUUACUUUUAUUUGCAACAUUUACAGUCCUUCAAAAUCCUUCCAAAGAAUUCUUAUACACAUUGGGGCCUUGGAGCUUACAUAGUUUUAAACUCAUUUUUGCCAUACAUCAGUUAUUCAUUCUGUGAUCAUUUAUUUUAAGCACUCUUAAAGCAAAAAAUGAAUGUCUAAAAUUGUUUUUUGUUGUACCUGCUUUGACUGAUGCUGAGAUUCUUCAGGCUUCCUGCAAUUUUCUAAGCAAUUUCUUGCUCUAUCUCUCAAAACUUGGUAUUUUUCAGAGAUUUAUAUAAAUGUAAAAAUAAUAAUUUUUAUAUUUAAUUAUUAACUACAUUUAUGAGUAACUAUUAUUAUAGGUAAUCAAUGAAUAUUGAAGUUUCAGCUUAAAAUAAACAGUUGUGAACCAAGAUCUAUAAAGCGAUAUACAGAUGAAAAUUUGAGACUAUUUAAACUUAUAAAUCAUAUUGAUGAAAAGAUUUAAGCACAAACUUUAGGGUAAAAAUUGCCAUUGGACAGUUGUCUAGAGAUAUAUAUACUUGUGGUUUUCAAAUUGGACUUUCAAAAUUAAAUCUGUCCCUGAGAGUGUCUCUGAUAAAAGGGCAAAUCUGCACCUAUGUAGCUCUGCAUCUCCUGUCUUUUCAGGUUUGUCAUCAGAUGGAAAUAUUUUGAUAAUAAAUUGAAAUUGUGAACUCAUUGCUCCCUAAGACUGUGACAACUGUCUAACUUUAGAAGUGCAUUUCUGAAUAGAAAUGGGAGGCCUCUGAUGGACCUUCUAGAAUUAUAAGUCACAAAGAGUUCUGGAAAAGAACUGUUUACUGCUUGAUAGGAAUUCAUCUUUUGAGGCUUCUGUUCCUCUCUUUUCCUGUUGUAUUGACUAUUUUCGUUCAUUACUUGAUUAAGAUUUUACAAAAGAGGAGCACUUCCAAAAUUCUUAUUUUUCCUAACAAAAGAUGAAAGCAGGGAAUUUCUAUCUAAAUGAUGAGUAUUAGUUCCCUGUCUCUUGAAAAAUGCCCAUUUGCCUUUAAAAAAAAAAGUUACAGAAAUACUAUAACAUAUGUACAUAAAUUGCAUAAAGCAUAAGUAUACAGUUCAAUAAACUUAACUUUAACUGAACAAUGGCCCUGUAGCCAGCACCUGUAAGAAACAGAGCAGUACCAGCGCUCUAAAAGCACCUCCUUGUCACUUUAUUACUCCCAGAACAACAACUAUCCUGACUUCUAAUAUCAUUCACUAGCUUUGCCUGGUUUUGUCUUUUAUGCAGAUAGAAUCAAUCAGUAUGUAUUCUUUUGUGCCUGGCUUCUUUCUCUCAGCCUUACAUUUGUGAGAUUCCUCUGUAUUGUGCUGAUUGUGGAUCUUUUCAUUCUCAUUGCAGAAUAAUGUUCUAUUGUGGGACUUAUUACAAUUUGUUCAUCCUAUUGUUGAUGGGCACUUGAGAACUUUCCAUUUUGGCGCUAUUACAAAUAGUGCAACUAUGAAUGUACUGCAUGUUACCAUCUUACUUGAGCCUUUAAUGGACUUAUUUCUUCAAAUCCUUCCAAAAAUUAUUAUAAGCAUUGAAAUUAUAGUUUCAAGCCAACUGUGGAUACCCUUACCCUUUCCUCCUUUAUCACAACCACCGUUACAAGUAUACUUAUAUUUCCCUAAAAUACAUUUAAAACUUACCUAAGUGACAUUUGUAGUUGGAGUAAUAGGAGCUUCCAGCUCUAAUAAAACAGCUGUCUCUAACUUAUUUUAUUUCCAUCAUGUCAGAGCAGGUGAAGAGCCAGAAGUGAAGAGUGACUAGUACAAAUUAUAAAAAGCCACUAGACUCUUCACUGUUAGCUUUUUAAAACAUUAGGCUCCCAUCCCUAUGGAGGAACAACUCUCCAGUGCCUGGAUCCCCUCUGUCUACAAAUAUAAGAUUUUCUGGGCCUAAAGGAUAGAUCAAAGUCAAAAAUAGCAAUGCCUCCCUAUCCCUCACACAUCCAGACAUCAUGAAUUUUACAUGGUACUCUUGUUGAGUUCUGUAGAGCCUUCUGAUGUCUCUAAAGCACUACCGAUUCUUUGGAGUUGUCACAUCAGAUAAGACAUAUCUCUAAUUCCAUCCAUAAAUCCAGUUCUACUAUGGCUGAGUUCUGGUCAAAGAAAGAAAGUUUAGAAGCUGAGACACAAAGGGUUGGGAGCUGAUGAAACUCACAAAUGAUGGUAGGAAGAAGCUCUCGACAAUACCCGUUGGCAAGGAGUCUGCCUCCAUGCUGCAGUGUUCGAGUGGAUUGUAGGUGCAAGAUGGAAAGGAUUGUAGGUGCAAGCUGUCCAGAGAAAAGAGUCCUUGUUCCAGCCCUAUUCUGCCACUCCUGACAGGGUGACCUUGGGUAUUUGCAAUAUUCCUUUGGGCCUCUGCUUCUCUCACCUAAAAAAAGAGAAUUAGAUUAUAUUGGUGGUUCUCAGCAAGAGAAGGAGUAUGUGUCCAAUGCUGCCUUCCCAUGAAUCUGUCUCCCAGUUAUGAAUCAGUGGGCAGGAUAAACUGAAAACUCCCAUUUACGUGUCUGAAUCGAGUGAGACAAAAUUUUAGUCCAAAUAACAAGUACCAAAGUUUUAUCAAGUUUGGGUCUGUGCUGCUGUUACUGUUAACCAUUUAAGUGGGGCAAAACCUUGCUAAUUUUCUCAAAAGCAUUUAUCAUUCUUGUUGCCACAGCUGGAGCUCUCAAACUAAAAGACAUUUGUUAUUUUGGAAAGAAGAAAGACUCUAUUCUCAAAGUUUCCUAAUCAGAAAUUUUUAUCAGUUUCCAGUCUCAAAAAUACAAAAUAAAAACAAACGUUUUUAAUACUAUUGCUUUUAUGCCUAGUCAACUCUG